CGUGUGUAAGGGGCAGGGUGUGUGAGGAGGAGAGGAACCCCAGCAAAGAGUAGUAAUAAUAAUGGCCACCGUCACACGAUAAUAUUCGAGUAAUAUGUGCGGGGACUUUACAAAGCAUCUCAUAUGCUUCAUUUUAACUUCUACUCCAAUCCUCCGAGGUGCGUACUGUUAUCAAACCCAUUUUACAAGAUAGGAAAACCGAGGCACGAAAUAGAUUAAGUGGCUUAUGCAAGGACACACGACUACUACGUGGCCUGGCCUGGCUUCGAACUUAGUUAUCUUAGUCCUAAGGCCCGUAAUUUUAACUUUGCUUUACCAAACAAAAACAGAAGAAGAAUGGCGUGUCAGAAGGAGGAGGACUGAGUGUGAUUUGAAGUGGAAGGAUGAUGAUAAACGAGAAGAGAAUGAUGAUGGGAGACGGAGUAGUGGGGAGGAGGACCUGAAUUUGGAAUCUUGCGGGCCUCCCCCUUCUAAAUCGCCGCCUCUUCCUUAGUUCUUGCGGCCCCAUAACUUUUUCUUGGUGUUCUAUGGCUUUAUGAAUGGAGGAGCCAACUCACAGACCUGGGCCAUUCGGGUGGUUUUAAGAAGUUUGAACUGCGGUUCAAUCCAGGGCAGUGCCUUGAGACACUGUUUGGAGGUAAGGGAGGGUCAGAGGAUCCUCUUAAACGCUGCUGCUAUUUAUUUCUUCAAACGUGCCACUUCCUUUUCUAUCAUAUCUAUGCACGGCAAAGCCUUUGUUCAGUCCUCUAGAAUAAGGAAGUGAUGUUUAUUGUUUCCUUGUACACUUGGGCUUAAACGAACAAAAUCAGACUCAACGUUUCUUUUCCCGAGCAAGGCCUUGAUUGCUUGCAGAGAAAACUUUCCUGUGGCUUUAUCAUUAGUUGCCCUUCAGAGCUUUCCUGUGUAAAUAAGAAGCUAUGUUUUGGAGAAGUUUACACCGUAGAUGAACGGGAGCGAUCUGAACAUACUGCACUGCAGGUCAACACAGAGCAGGGACUUCAGUAAUUCAUAGGUGUGAGUGUGUUUGUGAAAACCUUUCCUUCUUGCACAGUUUUCUGUGUAGCUCAUGUGGGAGUCAAGUUUUUAAGUCAGCCCGUGAGGCAAACAUUGUAUGUAAUAAAAAUUAACCCUUAAAAAUUCCUAGGAAGGUGCAACGCUUGAGAUUAGCAUCCUGUUUCUGACUACAUCCUGGACGGUUUUUCCUUCAGUUUUGAAACUUGUUACUGUUGCUUUGGUUGUAACCCAGAUAAGUAAUUAGAUUACCUUUAGGGGCUGUGUUGUGCAAAUAAGCAUAUUUGAAAGCCAUAGAGUUGUGAUGCGCUGUGAGAUGCUUGCCCUGAGGAGGCUUAAAAGGAGGAAGACAAACCCCUAUCUUAGGCUCAUUUUGGAGCAUGUGCUUACAAAGUGGAAAGUGGCAGGCAGAAUUGCUGGUAUGAUGAUGAUGAUGAUGAUGAUUUUUUUGAGACGUGCUCUUGCUCAGUCGCUGAGGCUGGAAUGCAGUGGCGUAAUCACAGCUCACUGCUGCAGCCUUGACUUCCUGGGGCUCAAGUGAUCCUCCCAGCUCAGUCUCCUGAGUAGCUGGGACUGCAGGCACACACUACCAUGCCUGGCUAAGUUUUUGUACUUUUUGUAGAGACGGGGUCUCACUUUGUUGCCCAGGCUGGUCUCGAACUCCUGGCUCAAGUGAUUCUGCAGUCUCAGCCUCUCAAAAGUGCUGGGAUUACAGGUGUGAGCCACUGCCCUUAUCCUGCUGGUAUUUAAGUUGCUAUUUUAUUUUAUUUUUUGGCCAGCAUAUGCAGUAAUUUGACUUGCUAAAUUAAAUGUGCAUAGUGCGAUUCCUCUUUAAUUUUUGAGUGGCACUACAUUCAGGGGCUUGCAAGCUAUUGUUUACUUCCCCACAGAUCCUAGCUAACUUUGGAGCAAAAAUGGCUUACAUAUUUUUGCCAACUGUCUGGCUUCGGCAGUCCCCAUAUAUAUGCCAGAUAUGUAUAACAGUGGUUAGCUUUUUAAAAACCAAUUCUCUUUUAAAUGGAAGUUAAAGGCGUCUUUUGGUUGUGUGGGGUUUUUUGUUGUUGUUGCUUUUGCUUUUACGGAAACAUCUCUCAAAAACUCAGGAGUGAUACACCCACUUCCUCCAAAGUAGUUAUGGUUAUGUUUGAAAUGACACCAAAAAUGAAGGGUAUUAUUUCAGUUAGGGAAAUAAGGAAGUACCACCGAUUUAACAUUAUAUGGGUAUAGAAAAUGGUUUUAAGGCCUUUUGCAGGGGAGAAAUCUUAAGCAAGUUUAGGAAUCUAAAAUUCUGAGUCGAAACAUUUUCUGAAUUAUGGUCAGAUAGUGUAAUUUACUCCACAUUCAUUCUGAACUUCUCUCUUUUCCUGAUCUUUAUUGUUCUUUUGCAAGCCUGUAAUAGAACAAAAACAAGAGAAGAAAUUUAUUCUGGCUUUAAGAAGUUUCUACUAUGUUUUUUGGGGGAGAUGCCACAUAGUCUACUUAAGUUUAAUUACUGUAAUUACAGAGAAAAAUCUGUGGAAGUAUAGGAUACCUUGAAUAAAUGGAAUCUUCAAGGUUUGCUGGCAAACCAACAGUUUGAUUUCUCAGAAGUUUCUUAGAGAAAUGAUGCCAGUUUUGUUUUGCUCCAGAUUCUCAUUGUUGCAUCUGCCAAUCUUGAAAAUAGGAAGCAAAGAUUUUCCUUGCUCUGUCCCUUGGGAACCACUUACAUUCGUUUUACUGUUUCUAGGAAAUUUUCUUUAAAUAUAUACAUUAGAGCCCACUAUUGUGUUGUGGAUCCAUGCAGUGGGCUUGCCUUAGAAAUCAGACCAAACAUUGUCUGGCUUGCACUGUAAAACUAGUUAGCUGAAGACGACUUCUCAGGUUUCUUCAGGAUGCCUGCAGCACUUGUGGAGAAUAGCCAGGUUAUCUGUGAAGUGUGGGCCAGUAAUCUAGAAGAAGAGAUGAGGAAGAUCCGAGAAAUCGUGCUCAGUUACAGUUAUAUUGCCAUGGACACAGAAUUUCCAGGUGUUGUGGUGCGACCAAUUGGUGAAUUUCGUAGUUCCAUAGAUUACCAAUAUCAGCUUCUGCGGUGCAAUGUUGACCUUUUAAAAAUUAUCCAGCUGGGCCUUACAUUCACAAAUGAGAAGGGAGAGUAUCCUUCUGGAAUCAAUACUUGGCAGUUCAAUUUCAAAUUUAACCUUACAGAGGACAUGUACUCCCAGGAUUCCAUAGAUCUCCUUGCUAACUCAGGACUACAGUUUCAGAAGCAUGAAGAGGAAGGGAUUGACACACUGCACUUUGCAGAGCUGCUUAUGACAUCAGGAGUGGUUCUCUGUGACAAUGUCAAAUGGCUUUCAUUUCAUAGUGGCUAUGAUUUUGGCUAUAUGGUAAAGUUGCUUACAGAUUCUCGUUUGCCAGAAGAGGAACAUGAAUUCUUUCAUAUUCUGAACCUUUUCUUCCCAUCCAUUUAUGAUGUGAAAUACCUGAUGAAGAGCUGCAAAAAUCUUAAGGGAGGUCUUCAGGAAGUUGCUGAUCAGUUGGAUUUGCAGAGGAUUGGAAGGCAGCACCAGGCAGGCUCAGACUCACUGCUGACAGGAAUGGCUUUCUUUAGGAUGAAAGAGUUGUUUUUUGAGGACAGCAUUGAUGAUGCCAAGUACUGUGGGCGGCUCUAUGGCUUAGGCACAGGAGUGGCCCAGAAGCAGAAUGAGGAUGUGGACUCUGCCCAGGAGAAGAUGAGCAUCCUGGCGAUUAUCAACAACAUGCAGCAGUGAUGGCGCCAGGCUCUGCAGGGUGGGCCUGAUCCCAGAGUGGUGCUUACUGUGCUGACUGUGUACUUAUCUUCCCCAAGAGAAAAUGCUUCUUUUGAGCACACUGUACCUACCAUCUGCAUUGAGCAGAAAGACUUUUGUUUUACUGAAGACAAAAGAUGUUUUUAUUUUAGACCCAGAAGAGAGGAGUUUGCUCUGAAUUUGUAAAUAAGUCUUCCCCAUUCCUCAUACUCGAGCCUCUCCUCUCUGGUUGCCUCCUGCCACCAGCAUCCAUGGCUCAUUUGACACCUUUUUAAAUAUCAGGACAAGUCUGAAACAAAGUAGUAAAAUGUAUAUAACUCUUACCUGUUGUCAUUCUUUUUCUUUUAAAUUUGUUGCUAAUCUCUGAUAAUGAAGAUUCUUACUCUGAUUCUCAGCUGAGCUGUGAGGGCUUCCAGGGAAAAUGGAACAAAAUGGUGUUCUUAGGUAAUGGGUUGUAGAUACUGAGUCUUCCUUUCCUUUUCUGACCCUUCUCGAGGACAUUUGCUUUCCUCACACUUUUGUAGUCUCUCUUUACAUAUUACUAUAUGGAAAUGAAUUGCUCUGUGCUGAAAUUUGAAGACCAGAUAAUGAAACUGAAAAGCAAACAAUUUUACUGAAUCUGUCUACCCUUCAUUCAUGAGAACUCCAGAAUGAGUGUUGACCACUGAAGCAUCUUUUAAGUCUGUGUUCCAUUGUGCCAUUCAGGUUUGCUGUCACAUAUGCAUCAUCUGAAAUCAUUUGAAAUUUUUGUACAAUAAAAUAUCCUGGAUUUGAUCCUGAAGGAAACUAGUAAGAUCAGAUUUUUGGGUCAUGUCUGUUGUAUUUUCAGUAAUGUGAUUUCAGAUGGUCAUCUGGAUUCUCCCACUUCUCUACUCCAUUAUUUCUCUACUUUUCCUUCCAGCAAACCUGAAACGUGAGGGAGAUGGAUUAAUGUGAGUAACAGGAAUGUGUCUUUAAAAAGCUAGAGUGGUUACAUUUAAUCAGGCAGUAAGAUAAUUUGGGUUCUUGAGUUGUUUUGGAGUAAUAUCCCACAACUGGGGUAGGAAGCUCAGGACUUUUUUCUUUAAAGCUAGUCAUUUCAAAAGCAUAUUGUAUUUUUUUGAAUGACUACAGUAUGGACAAUUUCAAAAACCAAAACCCACUUUGGAUUGGUGGAAGUAAAAACUGGUAACUCACUCAAGUGAAUGAAUGGUCUUGCAUUUUAAAAGCUUAUGGGAAACUCAAUUUGAAAUGAUUAGAAAAUGUCAAGUAUUAUAAGCUGGUAUUUAAGAUGCUUGUAAAUACUAUUUAUGUUUUUAAUUUUGUAAAAUAAAGAUUUCUUUUUAACCACUGGCA